GUCUUCUUUCUGGCAUUGGCGUUUUUUUGGUCUUACGCCCUAGGGUGGGGAGAGGACUCCGGUGCCUCCGGGUCUGGGCUGGGCCGCAAAGGGCGGGGCCUGGGCCCGGCGCGGGCCGGGAGCAGAGGCCGAGACCCUGCAGGUGUGUCGAAGGCUUUUGCGGGCGGGCAGGGCCUGGGAGGCGGGGUCUCGAGCCUGGAAGCCGCCUCCUGGCCCCGGAGCGGCCUCCGCGGAGGGCCCUGGGUGGGAGCCGCCUGGUGGGGAGGUUGGCUGGCUGCGCUGGCGCCCCUGCCCGGAAUGGCGUUUGCGCGACCUGCUUGAGGGGCGGCCAGAGGAGGCCUGCGGUGCUGGGCAGUGGGCGCCCGGAGCAGCCGCAUUGUGUGACGUGACCGGAGCCGCCAUGUGAGGCGCGCUGGCCGCUGCAGACGCGGCGCUCCAAAGCCGCAGGGACGUGGGCUCUGGUCCAGCGUCUGUAGGUGGUCCCAGUGCGGCUCGACGCGCAUCUGGCAAAUGAUGGGGGCCUUUGGGUACUGAAUAGGGUAAUAGAUGUAAAGUAUGAUACAGGACUCAAUAAAGGUGAUUCCUGGGGCUGCCAGCUAAGGUCCCUUAUGAUUUCUGCUCUGGCUUUGCAGUUUUCAGCCUUUCCCAAGAGCAGCAGAAAAUGAACAAGUUCCAGUGUGCUUUUUGGCCAUUUGUAUAUACUGUCAUCAAUUGGUAUAUGCAGGUGAUUGGUUCCAGGACCCCUGCAUGUACUUAAAUCCACACAUACUCAAGUCCUACAGUCAGCCCUUCAGAACCCACGUGUGCAAAAAAUUGGCCCUCCAUAUGUGUGGGUUUCCAAUCUUGCAAAUACUACAUUUUCAAUCUAUGUUAGGUUGAAAAUAAUCUGCAUCCAAGCCUGUGUUGUUCAAGGAAGAAUCCAUUGCCAAAUUCAAGGGACCCGUGACAUUAAAGGAUGUUAUUGUGGAAUUCACCAAGGAAGAAUGGAAGUUACUGACCCCUGCUCAGAGGACUCUGUAUAAGGAUGUGAUGCUGGAAAACUAUAGUCACCUUGUCUCAGUGGGUUACCAUGUGAAUAAGCCAAAUGCAGUCUUCAAGUUGAAGCAAGGAAAAGAGCCAUGGAUAUUAGAAGUAGAAUUUCCACAUCGGGGCUUCCCUGAAGACCUAUGGAGCAUUCAUGAUCUAGAAGCAAGAUACCAGGAAAGCCAAGCUGGAAAUUCAAGGAAUGGAGAACUCACAAAACAUCAGAAAACUCAUACCACAGAGAAAGCCUGUGAAUGUAAGGAAUGUGGGAAGUUCUUCUGCCAGAAGUCUGCCCUCAUAGUACAUCAGCAUACUCACUCAAAGGGCAAAUCCUAUGACUGUGAUAAAUGUGGGAAAUCUUUCUCUAAAAAUGAAGACCUCAUAAGACAUCAGAAAAUUCACACGAGAGAUAAAACCUAUGAGUGUAAAGAAUGUAAGAAAAUAUUUUACCACCUAUCAUCUCUCAGUAGACAUCUGAGAACCCAUGCAGGAGAGAAACCCUAUGAAUGUAAUCAGUGUGAAAAAUCCUUCUACCAGAAACCACAUCUCACAGAACAUCAGAAAACACACACAGGGGAGAAACCUUUUGAAUGUACUGAAUGUGGGAAGUUCUUCUAUGUGAAGGCAUACCUCAUGGUACAUCAGAAAACACACACAGGGGAGAAACCCUAUGAGUGUAAGGAGUGUGGGAAAGCCUUUUCCCAGAAGUCACACCUCACAGUACAUCAGAGAAUGCACACAGGGGAGAAACCCUAUAAAUGUAAGGAAUGUGGGAAAUUCUUCUCUAGGAAUUCACACCUCAAAACUCAUCAGAGAAGUCACACAGGAGAGAAACCCUAUGAAUGUAAGGAAUGUAGGAAAUGCUUCUACCAGAAGUCAGCCCUCACAGUACAUCAGCGAACUCACACAGGGGAGAAACCCUUUGAAUGUAAUAAAUGUGGGAAAACAUUUUACUAUAAAUCAGACCUCACUAAACAUCAGAGAAAACACACAGGGGAGAAGCCCUAUGAAUGCACAGAAUGUGGCAAAUCUUUUGCUGUGAAUUCAGUCCUCAGAUUACAUCAAAGGACUCACACAGGAGAGAAGCCCUAUGCAUGCAAGGAAUGUGGGAAGUCCUUUUCUCAGAAGUCACAUUUUAUUAUACAUCAGAGAAAACACACAGGGGAGAAGCCCUAUGAGUGUCAGGAGUGUGGGGAAACCUUUAUCCAGAAGUCACAACUCACUGCACAUCAGAAGACACACACAAAGAAGAGGAAUGCUGAGAAGUAAGAUGAGUUGGGAAAUUCUCUUGACUGAAUUAAUCCUUCAAAACAAUCAGAUAAUUCACACAAGAGGUACACCUUAUGAAUCGCAUCAAUAGAGGGAAAUUUUCAGCUACAAUCUUUGCUCUCUCUGUGUAUCAGCAAAUACAUAGAGAGAUUCUGUACAUUUAUUUGGGAGAAAAUUUUAUCAUAUUUUAGGCUUUUCUAAAUAUUAGAUAAUAUAGAUGGCAGAAGUCAUGCAAAUUGUAAAACAGGAAGGAAACCUUUCAGAAGUCAUACUUUUGUUUUGCAACAUAGAAGUCACACAGGAGAAAAAUCCUGUAAGUAAAACGAAUGUCAAGACAUUUUCUGUCAGGGCAGCCAGCUGUAGACAUCCAAAAGCUCACAAAUGAGAAGCUCCUUGAGUAUCUAGAAAUCUCUUUACACAAUUGGAGCUCAUGUACUAGAGAAUUCAAAGGGAUAACUGCAAAGACACUGGUAGAUAUAGAAGCCUUUAUUAAGAAUUGAUGUUUCAUUCAAUUUCAGAUCACUGGUACUUGGAUAGAUAUUUUAAAUAUUUGGAAGGUGUUCAAUAAAAAUUCAAAUAAUUUGUACUGAGGGAAACAGUUAUACUACAAAUCAUGUUGCAGAUCUGAUGCCGAGAUUGCUCUAUUUUAAAAGGAAACCUGCAAAUGUCUACAUAUAUGAAGCUUUUAAAAAGCACAAGUUAUCAGGCAACAUCAUUAAACAUACAUUAAAUGUCUGUUAGCAUAUAGGAUUUUGUGCGUAUGUGAGUGUGCUAUAACAUGUAACUUGCGGAUGUUCAGCGUGCAUGUGGAAUCCAUCCAUAAUGGUACAUAGCGAAAUAAUAUAAUCUUAGUUCAGUAACUAUUAUGUGUAUGAAGAUGUUGCACAUUAAGUCUCAGUAGUGACUCUGGUUGUUAAUAUUUGUAUUGUAAGUGUAAUAUUCCUUUUAAAUUAUAAGGCAUCUUUUUAUCCUUUUUUGUGUUUGUAAAUGGAUAUAGACAGUGGUAAUAACUAAUCCUUCAAAAAUAAGUUAAAAUGUUUUUGUAAAAUUUUCAAAUGUCAGUCAAGUUUUGCAUUAGGGACACAUUUAUAUAUAGCAAAAGCCUGAGCUGUUUUUAAACAGCUAAAAACAGUAGUAUUUAUUACAAUCUCCACAAUGAAAACAAAUAGUGCAAUGUAAGAAAUAUUAUGUAUCUUACUGUUGAUGUGUGAGCAGGGAGCAGAGCUAUCUGCAUUUGUAUUUAGUGUGAGAGUCCUAAAUGUUCUUCACCAACUUUUUCUUCCUCAUAGAAGCAACAUGGCAUAGUUAAGGGUGUGGACUCUGGGCUCCUGCUGCCUGGGCCCCGAUUCCAGCAUGGGGCAUGCUACUUAAUAUCUCUGUGCCUCAGUUCCCAUCCCAUAAAAGAGUAGUGAUAGUGACAACAUCUUAGGAUUGCUUUGAGGUCUAAAUGAGUUAACAUUUUCAAAGCACUUAGAAUAGUGUCUGAGACACAAGAGCUAUAUGUUAGAGGUUAUCAUCAUUAUUUGUAUUUUGUGAAUUACGCUGCAAAAAAAAAAAAAAUGUUGGCUACCCAACAUUCAUUCCCCACCUUCUUGCUGCCAGUGCCUUGAUUUGGUUGUUUGUUGUUUGUUUGUUUUCCUACAAGUGAUUUAGGGGCAGAUCCUGACUACACUAAGUCAGGGUUUGACAAAUGACAGUCCAUCAGACAGAUCUGGCCCACUACCCAUUUUUGUAUCCUGCAAGCUAAGAAUGGUUUUAUAUUUCUAAAUGGUUGAAAGAAUCAAAGAAUAUUGUGACACAUGAAAAUUAUAUGAUAUUCAAAUUUCAGUGUCCAUAAAUAAAGUUUUGAAAACAUGAAUACAAACAAAAAACACCUAUUUAUGUUUGACCUGUGGCUGUCUUUGCACUACCCCAGCAGAGUUGAGUAGUUGUAGCAGACACCACAUGCCCUUGAGCCUAAGAUCUAGCACUUUACAAAGUAAGUUUUUCUGUUACUUAGAGCUGAAAAUAAAAGCAAUGUAGAGUUACGCUUUUAUAAGUAUUUCAUGUUUCAGAAAUGAUGCAUACAGCAAUUUGUAGGUGGGUGGUUUUUUGCAGUAUAUUUAUUUUGUGCAUUAUAUUUAUAUGUUAAGAGCCUGAGCUUAGAAGUAUUUUUUUCAAAGAAAUGUGUUUUUUACUUGCUAAAUUGUCAUAACAUCAAAACAAGAAAUUUCUUGAUGGAAUGUAGCAGUAAACAUAUGAAAUAAACAUUGUCUAAAUUAAGUCGAAUUGUUCAUUGAUACUGCCCCACAGUAUUCCUUUGUUUUCUCCCAAAUCAAUGGCCAGUUUUCCCUGUAUCAUUUUAUAAUUUUCUUUCUAUCCCAUAAGAUACCAUUGGUAAGUCAUACUUAGCUAACGUAACCCAAUAACAAAAAACUUACAAUACCCAAUUCCAUCAGCUACAUUACUAGUAAUCUAUAAAAUUAUUGCCUGCACUUCAUGUAAUUGUCAUAUGCUGCUACAAUCUAAACCUGCCAGCGUCUUACUUCCCCUUCCUAAUAAAGACUUUCAUUGA